GAGCAUUUCCGGCAGCCAUCCCCGCGGUGCUGACAUCCCGGUUGUUCUUCUGUGCCGGGGGUCUUCCUGCUGUCAUGAAGGACGUACCGGGCUUCCUACAGCAGAGCCAGAACUCCGGGCCCGGGCAGCCCGCUGUGUGGCACCGUCUGGAGGAGCUCUACACGAAGAACUUUAUGAAAACUUUAUCAGUGAAUUUGAACACAGGUAAAAGCCUCUCAUCCGUUUUUCACUUUGAAAAUGAGUGCAUUGAUGCUCGGCGGUGCUCAAAGGCUGGUGGCUUUUAUUUCAGGGUGAACCCUUUGUCCCUCGUGGAAAUCAUUCUUCAUGUAGUUAGACAGAUGACUGAUCCUAAUGUGGCUCUUACUUUUCUGGAAAAGACUCGUGAGAAGGUGAAAAGUAGUGAUGAGGCAGUGAUCCUGUGUAAAACAGCAAUUGGAGCUCUAAAAUUAAACAUCGGGGACCUACAGGUUACAAAGGAAACAAUUGAAGAUGUUGAAGAAAUGCUCAACAACCUUCCUGGUGUGACAUCGGUUCACAGUCGUUUCUAUGAUCUCUCCAGUAAAUACUAUCAAACAAUCGGAAACCACGCGUCCUACUACAAAGAUGCUCUGCGGUUUUUGGGCUGUGUUGACAUCAAGGAUCUACCAGUGUCUGAGCAGCAGGAGAGAGCCUUCACGCUGGGGCUAGCAGGACUUCUCGGCGAGGGAGUUUUUAACUUUGGAGAACUCCUCAUGCACCCUGUGCUGGAGUCCCUGAGGAAUACUGACCGGCAGUGGCUGAUUGACACCCUCUAUGCCUUCAACAGUGGCAACGUAGAGCGGUUCCAGACUCUGAAGACUGCCUGGGGCCAGCAGCCUGAUUUAGCAGCUAAUGAAGCCCAGCUUCUGAGGAAAAUUCAGUUGUUGUGCCUCAUGGAGAUGACUUUCACACGACCUGCCAAUCACAGACAACUCACUUUUGAAGAAAUUGCCAAAAGUGCUAAAAUCACAGUGAAUGAGGUGGAGCUUCUGGUGAUGAAGGCCCUUUCGGUGGGGCUGGUGAAAGGCAGUAUAGACGAGGUGGACAAACGAGUCCACAUGACCUGGGUGCAGCCCCGAGUGUUGGAUUUGCAACAGAUCAAGGGAAUGAAGGACCGCCUGGAGUUCUGGUGCACGGAUGUGAAGAGCAUGGAGAUGCUGGUGGAGCACCAGGCCCAUGACAUCCUCACCUAGGGCCCCCUGGUUCCCCGUCGUGUCUCCUUUGACUCACCUGAGAGAGGCGUUUGCAGCCAAUGAAGCUGGCUGCUCAGACGGUCGACAUUGAAUUUGGGUGGGGGUUGGGAUCCUGUCUGAAGUACAGACUGUUCUUGCUCUAAAAACAGGACUGUCCCUGAUGGGAGCCAGGCCACAGGGAGGAGGCUUCUUUGUGGGUCUCUCCUGCAGAGGGUGGGGGUCUCAGGGUCUUAGGUGAUACGGGAGAGAAAGAACGUGCCAGGCAGGAGGCCCCCUGAAGUCUGUGUACUCCGAGGUGGAUCUCCAUCCCCAUCCACCUGUACGGACAUCUUUUCCGUUGCGGUUUGAGAAUGUUCCUAUAAUAAACCCCUCUGCUUUGUUCUU